AGUUGAAGCUCGGCGCUCGGGUUACCCCUGCAGCGACGCCCCCUGGUCCCACAGAUACCACUGCUGCUCCCGCCCUUUCGCUCCUCGGCCGCGCAAUGGGCACCCGCGACGACGAGUACGACUACCUCUUUAAAGUUGUCCUUAUUGGAGAUUCUGGUGUUGGAAAGAGUAAUCUCCUGUCUCGAUUUACUCGAAAUGAGUUUAAUCUGGAAAGCAAGAGCACCAUUGGAGUAGAGUUUGCAACAAGAAGCAUCCAGGUUGAUGGAAAAACAAUAAAGGCACAGAUAUGGGACACAGCAGGGCAAGAGCGAUAUCGAGCUAUAACAUCAGCAUAUUAUCGUGGAGCUGUAGGUGCCUUAUUGGUUUAUGACAUUGCUAAACAUCUCACAUAUGAAAAUGUAGAGCGAUGGCUGAAAGAACUGAGAGAUCAUGCUGAUAGUAACAUUGUUAUCAUGCUUGUGGGCAAUAAGAGUGAUCUACGUCAUCUCAGGGCAGUUCCUACAGAUGAAGCAAGAGCUUUUGCAGAAAAGAAUGGUUUGUCAUUCAUUGAAACUUCGGCCCUAGACUCUACAAAUGUAGAAGCUGCUUUUCAGACAAUUUUAACAGAGAUUUACCGCAUUGUUUCUCAGAAGCAAAUGUCAGACAGACGCGAAAAUGACAUGUCUCCAAGCAACAAUGUGGUUCCUAUUCAUGUUCCACCAACCACUGAAAACAAGCCAAAGGUGCAGUGCUGUCAGAACAUCUAAGGCAUUUCUCUUCUCCCCUAGAAGGCUGUGUAUAGUCCAUUUCCCAGGUCUGAGAUUUAAAUAUAUUUGUAAUUCUUGUGUCACUUUUGUGUUUUAUUACUUCAUACUUAUGAAUUUUUCCAUGUCCUAAGUCUUUUGAUUUUAGCUUUAUAAAAUCAUCCACUUGUCCCGAAUGACUGCAGCUUUUUUUCAUGCUAUGGCUUCACUAGCCUUAGUUUAAUAAACUGAAUGUUUGGAUUCCUCAGUUAUUGUUUACUUUUCAUCAUGGAAGCCUGUCACUGUAUGUAGGACAUAAUAGAACUUGAUCACUUGAAGCUCAGACCUAUUGGUCUUGAUCAAAUCAAACUAAGAAGACCUUAGAAAUAAGCUACCAUUUUGCCACAGAGCAGCUUAUAGGUAAUACACUCUUCUCUCAGUGCAGUGUACAUUUCCACAAAUCUAAGAAUUGCCCUAUAAACAUAGCAGGAUUUUGAGAGCUUGAAAAUUUUCCAUUAUUCUGGACAUGAAUUUCUAAAAUGCCUUAAUAGGUUUAUGUAGUUGAGUAAAUUUUGUUUUUUAAUUUUUGUAAGCAUCAAAGUUGAUUAGAGAGGGGGGCACUUUUUCUGGAGAAUUCUCUUAGUAAACACAAAAGAUUGUUACGGUUUCAUUAGUAGUAUGGUUGUGGGGCCAUAAGUUAAACAGUGCUGCCUGGUAGGCUGGGAACUGAAGAGACUUGUGGUAUUCCAUCUCGGGUGCCUCUGUUGGCAAUGAUCAGGCAGCCCAAAAGAUUUAAAUGAUCUAUAAUAAUUUCCAAGCGGUAGAUUAUGUGGCAUUUUAUUGCUCAGGCAAUAAUUGGUUUAAUGCUGGUAGUGUCAAAUUUUGAAGUGUUAAUUUUGUCUUAGAACCUUCCAGUAAGUGAAAUACAACCUAGUUUUAUCACCAUAUCCACCAGCAGGCAUGGAUAAUUAUUUUAACAAUGCUAAUAUUUGAGUUUUGCAGUAUAUUAUAGAAUAUAGUCCAGUUAAAUCUUUGGUUUCAGUAUGUCUGAAGAGUACAGUGAGAGGUUAAUUUCUGCUCAAGUGGUACCACUUAAAGGCAUGUAUUCUUUUAGUAUGUAAAAUGAAAUAGUACCUUGAGUUUAAAUAGAAUGCAUUUAGGCAUUGUAGAGAUCUGAAAUAGUUUUCUUCCACUACAUUGUUGAAAUCAAUGAAGCAAUUAGUUUCUCAUUCAGAAAUGUGCACACUAAUAUUUAGUUUUGCUUUCUCGUGGAUAAUAUUAAGCACUUACUCUGCAGUUUCCUGGAAGUUGUGUCAACUGCAGUGAUACUAUUCAGGAUGGUGGGAAAUCCCCAAAAAUAUGUAUGUGUGGGCUUGCUUAGAUUACUAUAUUUCAUAGUUAAUCUUUUGUCUCUUGCGGUGCUCAUGAUGUGUGGGGCACACGGAAGGCAUUGCUGUAGUCAGUCAUUUUGGUUUUCUUCUAUAGCCAUUUUAUUAUUUUAGUGUAUUAGUUAUGAAGAUAAUAUUAUCUAUUUGUAAAUUGCUACUUUGUAUUUUAUGCAUGCUCUGUAAUUUGAUUUUUUUUUAGUUAUUGAUUUGGAUUAUAUUCACAUUCUAAUAAACAGUUAUAGGGGGAUUAUUUCUUAUGCUGUCAGAUUACAUUUUUCCUUUGAGUGCUUUGGGUGCAGCCGUGGAAUCCUGAUGUAAAAGCAUAGGUUCUUGCAUUACUGAGUAAACAUUGAAUUGGGAGCAUCAGUGUGUGAAUUCAGCUUUGAUUUUAGAACUGCAGUUCAAUUAUGCUUUCCUUGGAAAAAGUAUGUCCAAAAACAUUAGGAAAGUAGUGUGUAUUUUCAUAUAUAACAGUGUCACCAGACCCAGGAAAAGAAACCAUCUCUAUUUUAUUGAAAGUUGGUGGUAGAUUUUUUACAAAGUAAGGAGAAAAGAGAAAAACUAAAUAGUGAAUUGAAAAUGAAUAAAGUAAACUUAGAAUUUUUACCCAAGUGUAGACUUAAAUGUUGCUUUGAGUAUGGCUGGAUCUUGGGAGAAUUCCAGGAAAUAUUAGGUAUUAGAAAAUGACUUUGAUUGCAUUUCAGCAGGUGUCUUUAUUCUGAGUAGUAUCUUAGGAGACAAACUGUCUCAAGCAAGAAACAAUAAAUUUUUAAAUAUUAUGACAGUUCAGGGCUUAAGGCAGUUUAGAAGUAUUUUGCUACUUGACCUUGAUUUUCAGUUAUUUUAACUUUGAAUUUUUUUUUUUUUUUUUGAGACGGAGUCUUGCUCUGUUGCCCAGGCUGGAGUACAAUGGCACCAUCUCAGCUCACUGCAAGCUCCACCUCCAGGGUUCAUGCCAUUCUCCUGCCUCAGCCUCCCGAGUAGCUGGGAUUAUAGGCGCCAGCCACCACGACUGGCUAAUUUUUUGUAUUUUUAGUAGAGACGGGGUUUCACCAUGUUAGCCAGGGUGGUCUCGAUCUCCUGACCUGGUGAUACACCCACCUCGGCCUCCCAAAGUGCUGGGAUUAAAGGCGUGAGCCACCGUGCCUGGCCUUGAAUUUUUUUUUAACCUGUUAUAUAGUCUCCUGAAUAGUUAGCCAUGGUGCCUUGAUUUAAUCUUAUGUCAUUGUUCUCAAAUGCCAUGAUUUCUCUUUAAUAGUAGUUGUCAUUAUGUAAGGGUAAGUUAUUGCCCAUUUAAUUGUAAUUAUAAGAAGAGGUGCCAGCUAGUGACCUUACAUCAGUGAUCUUUUAAGUUCUGAAGGGUUCUGCAGAAAAGUUACACUUCUUGAGUUUGGGUUGCCCAUCAGAGCUGGUCACAUUUCUUUGAUCAUUGAAAAAAUGAAUAUCUUAAUUUUUGUCUUUGCUGACUGGUAUUUAUAAAAUACAAAUGCUUUUAGUGGGUUGAGCUGUUGUGAUAAUCUCUUCCAUCUACCUUAGAGAAGAAGCUGUACUAUUUAGACAGUUUUGGCCAACACUAGAAGCAAAAGAAUUCAAAGGCUGGGUGGAUAUUUAAGAACUUAUUCUAACCUGUCAGGUUUCAAUUUGUGGGGCUUGGUUUAACAGAGGAAAAAAAUAUAAAUUGAUUUUCUGAUGUCUCACAAAUAUCACAUACCUGGAAAAAAAUUAAAACAAAAAAUGAAUUUUGUAAAAGGUUAUGUAUGACUUCCAUUUGCUCUGUAAAAAAAUGAACAAAGAUUGUGAAAGGAUCCUCUUCCACCACAUCAUUUAAUGGGUUAGCGGAACAGAUAGGGAGCUAUGACACUAGCACCAAAGAGAGAUUUUUCUUCUGGUUGGGUGGUGCUGGUGCCACGCCCCUUUCUGGGAUUUGACAAGUCUUUCCCACUCACCUAUACAAUAUGCCAAAUCAACUGGAGUUGUCAUUCUAAUGUUUUAAAGAAUGAUUGGGUUCCCCCAAACUGUAGGAGGUCGAUGGUAACAAUAAAGUGAUACAAAAUGCUUAUGUCAUUAUAAUUUAUGUAAGGGAGACCAUUAGGCUGAGAAUCAAUAUGAUUGAGGUUAUCUAUUCUCCUGAAAAGUGAAUUGGAGAAUAAAGAAAGAAUAUUUGAAAGGAUGUUGUGUACUAGGCAAUAUACUAGCAUGUAUUAGAAAAUACGGUAAACUGUGGGUUAGAAGAGUGAAAGUAGCUGGUAUGAUAGAGCACUGGACUGAGUAACGAAGAGAUUCUAGUCAUGGCUCUUGUGGUCAUUUCAUUUUUGAGCCUCACAUUCUUCCAAUUAAUGAGGGUACCAGAUUAAAUAAACUCUGGGGAUUCAUCCCAAUUCGAACUCUGUAAUUCUCUGAAUGAACUCUCUCUUCAAUUAAAGCCAAAUUAUUAACAUUUUAACUCAAGUUUAAAUUUAAUAGAGAAGUCAAAAUGAGGUAUGCACUUUGUGGAAUGUUUUUGGUCUUAUCACAAUAACCUGAUUAAAAUGGUGCCUUUAUUUCCAUGUUUACUCCUUUAAAUAAGAUGAAAGCUUUCAGAACAUUUAUUUGCAAAAUGACUGUCAAUAUCAACAAUAUGCAUCAAAGUACCAUAUAUGCUAAGGGAGAGGAGCACUUGAUGGGCUGCUAUGUUAACUGUAAAUUGAGAACUGCUUGUUUUAUGGCUUUUGCUGUUAAAAAAAAACUGCUGGCUUUUAAUAUGUACUUUAAAAUAUACUCAUGUCUGGGAGAGAACUUUUAAAAA